ACCUGGCACUGCCCCCAACCAAAGUCAUGAGGGCAAGGCUCCGGUUCCUGCCCUCACAGGGUCCCAGAAGCAAGGGCAGUGAGGACCUGGCCCACGUCCCUGGCACGGGCUGUCUGAUUCUCCUUCGCUGUGGCGGGAAGAUGGCCGGAUUUGAAGGCCUCCGCUGCUCACUGCUGUGCCUUGAUCGGCCUGGACGAGCCCGCCCACACCUCCAUCAUACCCAGUGUGAAGAGGGGCUGGGGACCCACCACUCCUGAGAACAGCAUCCUUGGGAAGACCCAGCUGUGAGUGCACAGCAGGCACAGUCCCUCAGGCCCAGGUGAGGAUUCAGCAGCAGAUGGGAUUCCACCCCAUCUGUGGCCUCUCCAGCUGUCCACAGGCCCUGCAAAGGCAGGGAGGUGGCAAAGGCCAGCCCAACCCAGCCCUCCACUCUGGGUACCCAGAGGAAGGCGCAGGCCGCUGGUUCCACAGCCCAUCACCUGGAGGUGAUGGAGGCCAACCCCAGCCCUGCCUGGAGGCCCUGGUGAGCUUGCCCAGCACUGCUCCAACCCCUCCCUGAACCCACAGGGCAGAGCCAGGGGUGGUCCAAUGGCCUGAGACGAGGGGACAGGGCUGGCCUAUUAAGAGGAGCCACCAGAGAAGGCACACCAGACACAGACUCCUGUCAGCUCAGGCGUCCUGGCCUAAGGAGGCAGGGCCCCCAAAAGAGCCAGGUCCUGGCACCAUCUCCGAGCUCCCAGCAGGCCUGCUGCAGGUCAGAAGGGCCACAUCCCAUCUUGGGUCCCUGACCUCAUUGGGCCUCACCUGAAAACAGGCACCCAGGCAGUGGCCAUGAACAGCCAGGCCACAAGCCUCGACAGGGGUGGGCCCCAGGUCACAGGGAGGGCGGUCUUUAUUUCUGGAAGGGCCCCGGAGCAGGAGGCUGCCUCUCUUCCACCCGUCCUUCUAUCCUCACGACAGGUGCUAUGGGGCCGCAGCAGCAUCAACAGCCUCUCUCAGCUGCUGCAGCAGCUCUUUGGGCUGUGGUGAGAACGCGCUGGUGUCCACUCUCUGGAAGUCGGGGUGCGCAACCAAGGAGGCCAGCACCUCUGUGAUGCGCCCAACAUCAAAGGCUGCCUGUUCGAAACCCAACCCAGCACCGUCCUCAGCGGCUGCCUCCCUCAGGACCAGGAGCCUCUUCUCAGCGAUGACCUUGAGGAAGUGGUAAAACUCUUCAAAGUUGAUGCCCGAGCAGGACCUCAUGAUGACCUGGGCAGAGGGAAGAGGCCAGUGAGCUAACACCAUGGACACAGUCCAAGCUGCAAAGGACCCGACAUGCGCCCAGUCCCCAAGGACGAAGAAGGGACCAUUAAGACAGAGGCACUGAGAAGCUGCGCGGUGACCAAGGGAGUCUGAGCCAUGCAGCCUAAAAGCCUCCCCCAGGAGGGUAGCCUCCAUGCGUAGCCACCCCACCUGGCAGUGGUGGUGCCAGUCGGGCAUGGAGUCCCUCCACUCGCUGACCUCCUCCUGCACGGCGCAUAGCUCCUGCUGCAAGAAGCGCCACAUGUUGGCCAGGUUGAAGCCAUUGACCCAGUUGUGGUUGAUGGAGAUGGUGUCAUCCUGGAAGGGGCACAGUGCAGGCAGGCCUGAGCCCAUGGCAGGUGCCCCCUGACCAACCCACAUCUCCUGCGCCAGGAACCCACUGUGGGGUCCAGCCCUCUGCAGCCAAGAGGGCCCUCCUGUCUCCCAGCAGGGCUUGCUCAGCAGGGAAGUGGGUGGCGGGCUCGGACCACCUCAGGCCACAGUGAACCCAGAGCAAGUAGACCCAGGGACCGGCAGUGGGUGAAACAGAGGCUAGGCCUCAGCGACACCACCUUGUGAAGGGGUCAGCCUCACCCAUGAGCCACCCCAUUCCAGCCCAGCUCUGGCUGGGAGAGUGGGGAGGUGGUGCUGCCGUCUUCCUGCAGGAAGGCCCCUGAUAGGGGGCAGGAGAAGCAGCACAUUACCAGGUUGUGCACCUGGUGGUGCCAGCCACUGGGCACAAACACCAUCUCGCCCGCUUCCUGCGUGAUCUCCAAGGGUGGGCCAGCAAGCUGGUUCCGUGGGUGCAGGUGUGUGUCGCAGAGUGCUGGGGAGGUCACGUCGUAGGGCAGGUUGCCGUGGCGGUCCCGCAGGGCCUCUUCCUGCCCUGGGGGGAAGAGGAGCCACUUCUUCCUCCCACAGACAUUGACAGACCAGCUGAAGGAGCGGAAGAUGUCAGCAUGGAACGGGGACCUGCGGCAGCAAGAGCGCCUGGUUCAUGCCUGUAGGGGCUGGUAUGGGCUUUGCUUGGCACCCCAGAGGCCUGGUCCAACUGAAGGAGGGGUGGCCCCUUGGUCUCAAGGGAUGGCACCCACUGUGAGGCCUGUGCCAAGCAGCCCCCCUCCUGCCACCCUGGGCCUCCCAGUCCGUUCUGUCACCAGGCCCCUUCGGGUUCCACUCCCACAUCCGUGGCCUCACCAGCUGCCCGCAGGCCCCGCGUAGACAAAGCGGUAGUCAUCCACAUCCAGUGCAUCCCAGAACUCAUUCAGCCAGUCGGACGAGAAGUACACAGGCAGGGUGAAAACGUCCUCCACCGGAAAGUCCCUGUGAGGAGGGCGCAAGGGCACCACCGACAGCACGUGAGGCACGAGGAGACUAGGGCAGCACGAGUGGGGCAACUGAGACCAAUCGGCUCCAGUGGAGCUUCCAGAUGGCUGCAGCCCCCAAAGAGCCCCAGACCCUCCUCUGAGCCAGACGCUGCUGGCGGGGGAGGGGGCGGGGCAGUCUGACUACAAUGGUUCUGCUUAUUAGAAAGUACUGAUCAUGCCUAUAAUCCCAGUGCUUUGAGAUGCUGAGGUGGAUGCAUCACCUGAGCUCAGGAGUUCAAGACCAGCCUGGGCAACAUGGUGAAACCUAGUCUCUUUAAAAAAAAAAAAAAAAAAAAAAAAAGCCGGGAGUGGAGACGCCUUCCUGUAAUCCCAGGUACUAGGGAGGCUGAGGAGAUCUCUCUCAAAAAAAAAGGAAAAAAAACCAUAUUGACCUCCCAAAGAACAACACUUGCAGCCAUGCGGAAGACAAUCCAGUUUCUUUUAAACUGAUUAAAGUGCCUCACGGGGAAAAAUAGCUCCGUUGUGCACCCAGGGGCCACCUUCAUCAGAAAGGCCUCUGGGUUCACGCAGCGCUAGGGAAGGCAGCGCCUCGGUGCGUCCCAAGCCCCAUUACCUGCACAAGUGCCAGUCUUUGAGGUAGAGACAGCCCCUGGGAGAGGAGUAGCCCGCCUGUAUGUACUCUUUCCAGUAGGUGAUGUAGUCUCUGAGAGUCAUGUGCUCUUUGGGGUUCGAGUUGUAUUCCUGGACCCCACAGUUUGCAACUGGUACAACCACGUCUCCUGAAAUGAAAGGCACGGUCCAUGCCAUCUCCCUGGGCCCCGUCCUCACUCCAAACCGUCUGCAGAGGAACUCUCCAGGGGCCACGCGCCUGGCCUCCCUCACCCUCCCUGGUGCCCCUCUCUAGGCGGGGGCCUCCCGGGCCUGGGUCCCGCCGGCCUUUCCUCCCCGCCCGGGGUCUGCGGCCGCCGCCCCACCGUAGGUCCGUAGCAGGUGGUCGAAGUCGGGCCUCCCCGCGGGCGUCACCCAGCGCCGCCGGCUGCCCCAGCCCUGCGUGAAGGCGCUGGAAAACACGCAGGGCAGGUUGGGCAGCAAGAAGCCCCGCACAAAGUCGGCGUAGGAGAAGGCGCCCGGCUCCGAGACGAAGGCUACCCGGCCCGGAGCCUGGCCGACGCCGGGGACAUCGACCCCCAGGCCUCGGAAGUGGCUGUCGGCGAGGGCGCGCGUCUCGCGGUCCAUCCAGCUCAGCACGGGUCGAAGGACCCUCCUCCUCACUUCCGCCGGAGCGGAAACGGUGAGGACCAGCCUCGGAACCAGAAGACGCAGGGCGCCGCGUUUCUGCCCCGCCAGCGCCUGGGGCUCCGGGCCUGCACGCAUGCGCGCGGCUCGCCGCGGUCUUCACUGCGCAGGCGCCGAGCGGCCGAGGCGCCGCGGUCGGCUCUGGGACUCGUCUGGCGUCCCUCAGAGGCAGAAGAGGCCUGGACCUUGGCGCACACAGACCCAGGAACAGAUGAGCAGGGAUGUCUGCAUCCACACCUGGCCGUGCACCUACUACCUGGAGCCCAAGAGGCGAUGGGUUACUGGACAGCUGUCCUUAACAUCGCUGUCGCUCAGGUUCAUGACUGACAGCACUGGAGAGAUUCUGGUCAGCUUCCCCCUCUCCAGCAUAGUUGAGAUCAAGAAGGAGGCUUCACAUUUUAUCUUCAGCUCCAUCACCAUCCUGGAGAAGGGCCAUGCCAAGCACUGGUUCAGCUCCCUGCGGCCAAGUCGAAAUGUGGUCUUCAGCAUCAUCGAGCAUUUCUGGAGGGAGCUGCUGCUGUCUCAGCCUGGAGCCGUGGCAGACGCAUCUGUCCCAAGGACCCGGGGCGAGGAGCUGACGGGACUCAUGGCUGGAUCCCAGAAACGCCUGGAGGACACGGCGAGGGUCCUGCACCACCAGGGCCAGCAGCUGGACAGCGUCAUGAGAGGCCUGGACAAGAUGGAGUCAGACCUGGAGGUGGCGGACAGAUUGCUGACAGAACUGGAAUCUCCUGCUUGGUGGCCCUUUAGCUCCAAGCUUUGGAAGACACCACCGGAAACAAAGCCCAGGGAAGAUGUCUCCAUGACCAGUUGUGAACCCUUUGGGAAAGAAGGGAUACUGAUAAAAAUUCCUGCUGUUAUUUCCCACAGAACAGAGUCUCACGUUAAACCAGGGAGGCUCACCGUCCUUGUGUCUGGGUUGGAAAUACAUGACUCCAGUUCUUUGCUCAUGCACAGGUUUGAAAGAGAAGACGUGGACGACAUCAAGGUCCACUCACCUUACGAAAUUAGCAUCCGCCAGCGGUUUAUUGGAAAGCCAGACAUGGCCUAUCGUUUGAUAUCUGCCAAGAUGCCAGAGGUUAUCCCCAUUUUAGAAGUGCAGUUCAGCAAGAAGAUGGAGCUGUUAGAAGAUGCAUUGGUGCUCAGAAGCGCAAGAACCUCUUCCCCCGCAGAGAAGAGCUGCUCAGUCUGGCAUGCAGCAUCUGGGCUGAUGGGCCGUACCCUGCACCGUGAGCCACCCGCAGGAGACCAGGAGGGCACAGCACUGCACCUGCAGACAAGCCUGCCAGCCCUUUCUGAGGCAGAUACCCAGGAACUAACCCAGAUCCUGAGGAGGAUGAAGGGGCUGGCCCUGGAGGCCGAGAGUGAGCUGGAGAGACAAGACGAAGCCCUGGAUGGCGUUGCAGCAGCUGUGGACAGGGCAACCUUGACCAUCGACAAGCACAACAGGCGGAUGAAGAGGCUGACCUAGGGGCAGAACGUCCCUGCAUUCCUGUCUCACCCUGCACAUCCCGCUGAGAUGGAGGGCUGGGCGGCAGUGCCAGGGCUGCAGAGGCCUGUGGCCCUCCGGAGUGGUCUUCCUCUGGAUGGGGCUGCUACUGUGGGGCUGCUUCUGCACCAGGGGCCUCCCCAGGUGUGCACCAUGCCUGCCUCCCACUUGGCUGUCCCUGCUGCUGGGCAGGACCCGGCCACAUGUUCUGCGGAUGCUGCAGAAGUGUGGACCAUGGCGGGACCCCAAGGACACUUGGCACAGGCCUGGAAGAGGCCGCCCUCGUCUUGUCUCGGCUCCCUUUCAUGGACAGACUGGCCUUCUUAGCUGUACUAUAAAUUUGUGAGUGAAGUUAGAGCCCAGCUCACUUAGCCAGCUCACUUUGAGGGCAUCCUAUAAACACCCAACUGUUCUUUUAUCGUCUCGGUUUUAGCCAAAAGUGAAAUUAGCAUGACUGCAUCUUUCAAACAAAAAUAUUGAUUUCUGCUUUUAGGGCCCCGUUUCCAUCCAGAAAUAAAGGGAAAUGCUGGCUUCA